AGGUGGCGUCAGGUCAUUUCAGGCUCUUAAGUGUGGGCGUUUGGUAUCCGGCAUGGCUGCUACCUGUUUCUGGCUGGAGCCUCGGACACUGGCUCACUGCAGUUGGUGGUGUCGACAGUGGUAGAAGGGCAACCAGUAGCGGGAGCUUCUCCUGCCAGGCAGGAAGACGAGUAGAAGGGAGCAGCACCGACGCAUGCUGGAGGCUGGAGCCUGAGCCCCUGGGGCUCGCCUUGCUGUGUUUGGUGGUGACGUGGGACACUGCAGCUCGGCCAGAGUGGUAGAAAUGUCCUGGUGUAGGCUUUUCUGGCUUUGCCCGUCUAGCUGCUCCAAGCCAGGCUGGAGGAGGAGGAGAAGGAAUCACCUGUGGUACGCUGGAGCCUGCAUGUGGCGUGACUCUGCAGCUCGCCUCGUGUGACUGAUGGCAGCCACGGAGACUGCAGCUCGACAGGAGUGAGGCUUCUCAGUGGCUUGAAAGCUCAGCUGACUCCCACGAAGUUUGCCGGAACUCAAGGCUGUCAGUGACAUUCGUGGCGCCAAGACUUAAGCAGGCGCGUUGCAUGCAUCGGCCAGUGUCUGUGCCACGUGCCCUGACGCCACCUGAGAUAAGCACGCCGCACGCGCACGCGCACGCCUCGCGCGCACGCCCGGCAGCAGCUUGGCUGGCUUGUAACGGCUUGCACGCGCACGACGCACGCGCAUAACGGUUUGGCCGGCCUGUAACGGCUUGCACGCGCACGCCGCACGCGCGUAACGGCUUGGCUGGCCUGUAAUGGCUUGCACGCGCAUGCUGCACGCGCUUUAACGGCUUGGCUGGCCUGUAGCGGCUUGGCUUGGCUUUGCGUUCUUGGCUUGGCUUGGCGUUGGUAGCUUGGAUUGACGUUUCCUGCUUGGAUUGACGUUUUCUCUCUCGUGUUCCUUUGCUGGGCUUGACCUUUUCUCUGCUGGGUUUGGCAUUCCCUUGGGUGGGCUGGGUGUUUUCUUGGGGGCGGGGGUUGGCCCUUUCUGGGGUGGGCGUGGGGUCGCCCAGGGGGGGCGUGGGCUUUCCUCGGGUGGGUGUGGGUUUUCCCUGGGUGGGGUGGGCUGGGCUGGAAUCCCCUGCUGGGGUUGGCAGGUUUUGGCUGGGAUUGACUUUUCUCUUCAAACAGAUUGGAAACCCGGAGUUACCUGCUAGUUGGUGAAACUGGUUGGUAGACGCGAUCUGUUGGCUACUACUGGCUUCUCCUGGCUGUUAAAAGCAGAUGGUGGUUGAGGUUGAUUCCAUGCCGGCUGCCUCUUCUGUGAAGAAGCCAUUUGGUCUCAGGAGCAAGAUGGGCAAGUGGUGCUGCCGUUGCUUCCCCUGCUGCAGGGAGAGCGGCAAGAGCAACGUGGGCACUUCUGGAGACCACGACGACUCUGCUAUGAAGACACUCAGGAGCAAGAUGGGCAAGUGGUGCCGCCACUGCUUCCCCUGCUGCAGGGGGAGUGGCAAGAGCAACGUGGGCGCUUCUGGAGACCACGACGACUCUGCUAUGAAGACACUCAGGAACAAGAUGGGCAAGUGGUGCUGCCACUGCUUCCCCUGCUGCAGGGGGAGCGGCAAGAGCAAGGUGGGCGCUUGGGGAGACUACGAUGACAGUGCCUUCAUGGAGCCCAGGUACCACGUCCGUGGAGAAGAUCUGGACAAGCUCCACAGAGCUGCCUGGUGGGGUAAAGUCCCCAGAAAGGAUCUCAUCGUCAUGCUCAGGGACACUGACGUGAACAAGAAGGACAAGCAAAAGAGGACUGCUCUACAUCUGGCCUCUGCCAAUGGGAAUUCAGAAGUAGUAAAACUCCUGCUGGACAGACGAUGUCAACUUAAUGUCCUUGACAACAAAAAGAGGACAGCUCUGAUAAAGGCCGUACAAUGCCAGGAAGAUGAAUGUGCGUUAAUGUUGCUGGAACAUGGCACUGAUCCAAAUAUUCCAGAUGAGUAUGGAAAUACCACUCUGCACUACGCUAUCUAUAAUGAAGAUAAAUUAAUGGCCAAAGCACUGCUCUUAUAUGGUGCUGAUAUCGAAUCAAAAAACAAGCAUGGCCUCACACCACUGUUACUUGGUGUACAUGAGCAAAAACAGCAAGUCGUGAAAUUUUUAAUCAAGAAAAAAGCGAAUUUAAAUGCACUGGAUAGAUAUGGAAGGACUGCUCUCAUACUUGCUGUAUGUUGUGGAUCAGCAAGUAUAGUCAGCCUUCUACUUGAGCAAAAUAUUGAUGUAUCUUCUCAAGAUCUAUCUGGACAGACGGCCAGAGAGUAUGCUGUUUCUAGUCAUCAUCAUGUAAUUUGCCAGUUACUUUCUGACUACAAAGAAAAACAGAUGCUAAAAAUCUCUUCUGAAAACAGCAAUCCAGAACAAGACUUAAAGCUGACAUCAGAGGAAGAGUCACAAAGGUUCAAAGGCAGUGAAAAUAGCCAGCCAGAGAAAAUGUCUCAAGAACCAGAAAUAAAUAAGGAUGGUGAUAGAGAGGUUGAAGAAGAAAUGAAGAAGCAUGAAAGUAAUAAUGUGGGAUUACUAGAAAACCUGACUAAUGGUGUCACUGCUGGCAAUGGUGAUAAUGGAUUAAUUCCUCAAAGGAAGAGCAGAACACCUGAAAAUCAGCAAUUUCCUGACAACGAAAGUGAAGAGUAUCACAGAAUUUGCGAAUUAGUUUCUGACUACAAAGAAAAACAGAUGCCAAAAUACUCUUCUGAAAACAGCAACCCAGAACAAGACUUAAAGCUGACAUCAGAGGAAGAGUCACAAAGGCUUGAAGGCAGUGAAAAUGGCCAGCCAGAGAAAAGAUCUCAAGAACCAGAAAUAAAUAAGGAUGGUGAUAGAGAGCUAGAAAAUUUUAUGGCUAUCGAAGAAAUGAAGAAGCACGGAAGUACUCAUGUCGGAUUCCCAGAAAACCUGACUAAUGGUGCCACUGCUGGCAAUGGUGAUGAUGGAUUAAUUCCUCCAAGGAAGAGCAGAACACCUGAAAGCCAGCAAUUUCCUGACACUGAGAAUGAAGAGUAUCACAGUGACGAACAAAAUGAUACUCAGAAGCAAUUUUGUGAAGAACAGAACACUGGAAUAUUACACGAUGAGAUUCUGAUUCAUGAAGAAAAGCAGAUAGAAGUGGUUGAAAAAAUGAAUUCUGAGCUUUCUCUUAGUUGUAAGAAAGAAAAAGACAUCUUGCAUGAAAAUAGUACGUUGCGGGAAGAAAUUGCCAUGCUAAGACUGGAGCUAGACACAAUGAAACAUCAGAGCCAGCUAAGAGAAAAGAAAUAUUUGGAGGAUAUUGAAAGUGUGAAAAAAAGGAAUGAUAAUCUUUUAAAGGCUCUACAAUUGAAUGAGCUCACCAUGGAUGAUGAUACCGCCGUGCUCGUCAUUGACAACGGCUCUGGCAUGUGCAAGGCCGGCUUUGCGGGCGACGAUGCCCCCCGGGCUGUCUUCCCUUCCAUCGUGGGGCGCCCCAGGCAGCAGGGCAUGAUGGGGGGCAUGCAUCAGAAAGAGUCCUAUGUGGGCAAGGAGGCCCAGAGCAAAAGAGGCAUCCUGACCCUGAAGUACCCCAUGGAACACGGCAUCAUCACCAACUGGGAUGACAUGGAGAAGAUCUGGCACCACACCUUCUACAACGAGCUGCGUGUGGCUCCCGAGGAGCACCCCGUCCUGCUGACCGAGGCCACCCUGAACCCUAAGGCCAACCGCGAGAAGAUGACCCAGAUCAUGUUUGAGACCUUCAACACCCCAGCCAUGUACGUGGCCAUCCAGGCCGUGCUGUCCCUGUACACCUCUGGCCGUACUACUGGCAUCGUGAUGGACUCUGGUGACGGGGUCACCCACACUGUGCCCAUCUAUGAUGGGAAUGCCCUCCCCCAUGCCACCCUGCGCCUAGACCUGGCUGGGCGGGAACUGCCUGACUACCUCAUGAAGAUCCUCACCGAGCGUGGCUAUAGGUUCACCACCAUGGCCGAGCGGGAAAUCGUGCGUGACAUCAAAGAGAAGCUGUGCUAUGUUGCCCUGGACUUCGAGCAGGAGAUGGCCACGGCGGCCUCCAGCUCCUCCCUAGAGAAGAGCUACGAGCUGCCCGAUGGCCAGGUCAUCACCAUCGGCAACGAGCGGUUCCGCUGCCCCGAGGCACUCUUCCAGCCUUGCUUCCUGGGCAUGGAAUCCUGUGACAUCCAUGAAACUACCUUCAACUCCAUCAUGAAGUCUGAUGUGGACAUCCGCAAAGACCUGUACACCAACACAGUGCUGUCUGGUGGCACCACCAUGUACCCUGGCAUGGCCCACAGAAUGCAGAAGGAGAUCGCUGCCCUGGCGCCUAGCAUGAUGAAGAUCAGGAUCAUUGCUCCUCCCAAGCGCAAGUACUCCGUGUGGGUCGGUGGCUCCAUCCUGGCCUCGCUGUCCACCUUCCAGCAGAUGUGGAUCAGCAAGCAGGAGUAUGAUGAGUCAGGCCCCUCCAUUGUCCACCGCAAAUGCUUGUAGGUGGACUCUGACUUAGUUGCGUUACACCCUUUCUUGACAAAACCAAACUUCUCAGAAAACAACAUGAGAUUGGCAUGGCUUUAUUUGUUUUCUUGUUUCAUUUUUUGUUUUGUUUUUUAUUGGCUUGACUCAGGAUUUAAAAACCGGAAUGGUGAAGGUGACAGCAGUCGGUUGGAGGAAGCUUCCUCCAAAGUUCUACAAUGUGGCCAAGGACUUUGAUUGUACCUUGUUCUUCUUUUCAAUAGUCAUUCCAAAUAUUGUGAGACGCAUUGUUUCAGGAAGCCCCUUGCCCUGCUAAAAGCCACCCUACUUCUCUCUAAGGAGAAUGGCCCAGUCCUCUCCCUAGUUCACACAGGGGAGGUGAUAGCAUUGCUUUUGUGCAAAUUACAUAAUGCAAAAUUUUUUGAAUCUUCGCCUUAAUACUUUUUAAUUUUGUUUUAUUUUGAAUGAUCAGCCUUCGUGGCCCCCCUCUUUUGUACCCCAACUUGGGGUGUAUGAAGGCUUUUGGUCUCCCUGAGAGUGGCUGGAGGCAGCCAGGGCUUACCUGUACUCUGACUUGAGGAGAGAUGGAUAAAAGUGCACACCUUAAAACAAAUUGAGGAAGCACAGUAUUUCAGUACAGUGGACAGCUUAGCAUGUUGACAACUGAGAAUAAAAUGCUCAGUUCUGAACUGGACAGUGUAAGACACAACGAGGAAACACUGGAAAUGGAAAUUCAAUUACGUCAUUGUAGACUGGCUGCUGCUCUACAUGAUUGUGACCAAAGUCAGAUAGCUGAAAGAGACUUCUUUCCAGAGAACAAGACAUGAACAGGUUUAUUUACAGAAGACAAUGAAUUCUCAUUUAUCUCACCUAAAAGAGAACAGAUUCUUUCUCAACAAGUCUAAUGAAGACAGUAAAAUCAACAGGCUAAAAAUUAAGCUCCACGAAACAAGAUAAAACUCUGAGAGAAAAGACGGGGCAGGCCGCCAUCUUUCCCGUUCAGGCAACUUAGUCAUUCCAGCCUGCGGGCUUUGGAGAGUACAAACCGAGGAGGGACAGAAGAGAUCCCACAGCACAGCAUAGCUGCUUUACCAAAUCAUGGCCAGACUGCUUCUGUAAGCAGGCCCCUGAUCCUGUUCCACCUCACUGGACAGGACCUCCCAACUGGGGCCUCCAGCUACCCCCACCAGCAUUCCUUGGCCAAUGGAAAUGUGAAAUGUUCCUGGGACAGAGCUCCCGGAGAGGGGCAGGCCCCCACCUUUGCUCUUUCGGUGACUAGCCAUUCUGGCCUGCGGGCUUUGGAGAGCCCAAGCUGACAAGGGGUGGAAGAGGUACCUCAGCACAGCACAGCCACGCUACAAAAACGUGGCCAGACUCUUGUUUACGUCAGUCCCUGAUCACAUUUCUAGUCAGCGGGUGAAGUCUUUCAACCAGGGUCUCUGGCUACCUUGACUGCUGUUCUCUGGCCGACAGAGGUCUCAGGCCUCACUGAGUCAGAGCUCCCAGGGGGAGGACCAGAUUGUCAUCUUUGCUGUUUGGGCGACCCAGGCAUUUCAGCCUUAGGGCUUCAGAGUGUCUGAGGCGGACCAGGGGCUGAAGUGAACCCCCAGCACAGCACAGCUGCUCUAUAAAAACGUGGCCAGACUUUUUUUUUUGAAGCAAGUCCCUGUUCUCGUUCGUCCUGACUAGGUAAGACUUCUCAACUUGCCUCCAGCCACAUCUUAUAGGUGUGUUCAGAUUGGCAACAGGUUCGUACCUCAGUGGUACAGAGCUUCCAGAGGAAGGGGCAGACUAUCAUCUUCCGUGGAAAAUACAAGGUAAUUAGGGACUGGAGGGGACCCCCAGCAUACCACAGCAGCCCUACAGAAAAGUGGCCGGGCUCUCUACUUGAUGGGCAGAUCCUCCUGGCCUGGGUCUCUAGCCAGCCCACCACUGGAGCUAUCAAGCCAGUAGCAACUCUGCAGUUCCUGGGACAGAGCUUCCAGGAGCAAAUGAAAUCCUUUCUGCCACUGCCUCUGCAGUGGAACUGCCCUUGCUACCCUCAGAAGAUGCAAGGGUGCAAAGACCCUAAGUGCCCUAUCAACACCUCCAAUAAGCUGCAGUUGACCCAAAGAACAAGCCAGUCCAUCUCCCACGGGUACCACACACCCUCCACUACUCAUCACCAGACAGGGAACCCUGGCUUGGGCCCACAGCACAGACCCUCCAUCCUGGGCUGAUUACACUAAGUGAUUGCUAACUCACAUGUCUCUGGGAUGGAGCACCCAGGAAACAAGCAAAGUGGUGGAGCAGCAAGUCAGGUGAUGUGGAGCCCAGAGGUCAGGGAUGGCUGUCUCUCUAGGGUCCACUUGCCCUUGUGAGACACUUUAUCCCAGCACUUUAGGAAUGCUGAGGUCAUACCAGCCACAUCUUAUAUGCAAGAUUGCCCAGCAGAGAUCAGGUCCGAGAGUUCCCUUUUUAAAAAAAGGAGACUUGCUUAAUAAAAGAAGUCUAGCCACGUUUGUGUAGAGCAGCUGUGCUGUGCUGGGGGUUCACUUUUGAGAGAGUUCUCCUCUGAGACCUGAUCUCUGGAGGCUGGGCAGUCUUGCACUUGAGAUGGGGCUGGUCUGAUCUCAGCACUCCUUAGUCUGCUCGCCUCUCCCAUGGCCCCAGCCUGGCCACACCUGCUUACGGGGCACUCUUAGAUGCCCACACCAUAGCUUCCAUGCUAGUGGACUGUACCAUAUCAGUGGAGAGCUGCAGCAAGGUGGCCUCUAGAGCCACGCACCAGCCUGCACAUUGCCUCUCCAUACGGCAGCCCUUUAUUUGGAAACUUCCUAAAUCACUUUGCUGUGUGUGUUUACACGGGUGGGUUUUGCUUUACUUGCCCUGAGAGCACACGGGAGUGCAGCACACACCCCAACCCACAUCAACUGCCAUUGAAGAAAAGAAAUUUCAGCCCAGAAUUUCAUGUCCAGCAAAAUUAAGCAUCAUAAGUGAAGGAGAAAUAAGAUCCUUUUCAGACAAGCAAAUGCUGAGGGAAUUUGGUAUCACCAGAUCUACCUUACGAGAGCUCCUGAAGGAAGCACUAAAUAUGGAAAGAAAAGAUCAUCACCUGCUACUACAAAAACACACUGAAGUACACAGUCCAAUGAUGCUAAAAAGCAAGCACAUAUGUAAGUCUGCAAAAUAACCAGCUGACAGCAUGACGACAGGAUAAAAUCCACACAUACCAUUACUAACCUUAAAUGUAAAUGGGCUAAAUGCUCCCAUUGAAAGACACGGGGCAAGCUGGGUAAAGAACCAAGACCCACUGGAGUAUGCCGUCUUCAAGCAACCCAUCUCACGUGCAGUGCCAUACAUAGGCUCAAAAUAAAGGAAUGGAGAAAAAUAUUUCAAGCAAAUGGAAAACAGA